GGAGGGGAGGGGCGCGGCCGCCGGACGCGCCCUCGCAGCUUCCGCCGGGCCCCUCCGGAAAUCCCGUAUCGUAGGGCGACGGCGGCUUAGAAAGUGCUUCCUGGAGCGCAGACGAGGUCAUGAAUCAUGUGACGGUGGCUUGAGGAGGAACCUGUCUUUAAAGCUGUCCCUGAAGUGACAGCGGAGAGAACCAGGCAGCCCAGAAACCCCAGGCGUGGAGAUUGAUCCUGCGAGAGAAGGGGGUUCAUCAUGGCGGAUGACCUAAAGCGAUUCUUGUAUAAAAAGUUACCAAGUGUUGAAGGGCUCCAUGCCAUUGUUGUGUCAGAUAGAGAUGGAGUACCUGUUAUUAAAGAGCAUGCUUUGCGACCUGGUUUCUUAUCCACUUUUGCCCUUGCAACAGACCAAGGAAGCAAACUUGGACUUUCCAAAAAUAAAAGUAUCAUCUGUUACUAUAACACCUACCAGGUGGUUCAAUUUAAUCGUUUACCUUUGGUGGUGAGUUUCAUAGCCAGCAGCAGUGCCAAUACAGGACUAAUUGUCAGCCUAGAAAAGGAACUUGCUCCAUUGUUUGAAGAACUGAGACAAGUUGUGGAAGUUUCUUAAUCUGACAGUGGUUUCAGUGUGUACCUUAUCUUCAUUAUAACAACACAAUAUCAAUCCAGCAAUCUUUAGACUACAAUAAUACUUUUAUCCAUGUGCUCAAGAAAGGGCCCCUUUUUCCAACUUAUACUAAAGAGCUAGCAUAUAGAUGUAAUUUAUAGAUAGAUCAGUUGCUAUAUUUUCUGGUGUAGGGUCUUUCUUAUUUAGUGAGAUCUAGGGAUACCACAGAAAUGGUUCAGUCUAUCACAGCUCCCAUGGAGUUAGUCUGGUCACCAGAUAUGGAUGAGAGAUUCUAUUCAGUGGAUCAGAAUCAAACUGGUACAUUGAUCCACUUGAGCCGUUAAGUGCUGCCAAUUGUACAAUAUGCCCAGGCUUGCAGAAUAAAGCCAACUUUUUAUUGUGAAUAAUAAUAAGGACAUAUUUUUCUUCAGAUUAUGUUUUAUUUCUUUGCAUUGAGUGAGGAACAUAAAAUGGCUUGGUAAAAGUAAUAAAAUCAGUACAAUCACUAACUUUCCUUUGUACAUAUUAUUUUGCAGUAUAGAUGAAUAUUACUAAUCAGUUUGAUUAUUCUCAGAGGGUGCUGCUCUUUAAUGAAAAUGAAAAUUAUAGCUAAUGUUUUUUCCUCAAACUCUGCUUUCUGUAACCAAUCAGUGUUUUAAUGUUUGUGUGUUCUUCAUAAAAUUUAAAUACAAUUCGUUAUUCUGUUUCCAAUGUUAGUAUGUAUGUAAACAUGAUAGUACAGCCAUUUUUUUCAUAUGUGAGUAAAAAUAAAAUAGUAUUUUUAAAAAUAUAGUUUGAGCACUGUAUAGGUCCUUUUUUUGUUCAGACUUUUUCCAAAAAUCUAAACAUAAUUAAUAUACUCUUUCAGCCACAUGAAUAAAUAAUGAGUGUUUCUUGUAGGUAUUGGUUUGGAGAUUGUUUUACGGUAGUAUGAACUGUUAACUGGAAAAGAAACCUGAGAUUGCAGUCAGCCAAGAUUGUGCCACUGCACCCCAGCCUGGGCAACAGAGACUCCGUCUCAAAAACAAAAAAGAAAAGAAACCAAGAAACCUCAGGCAUGAACCUAAUUUAAUCUCCAUGAAAGAGGUACUACAGUUCUAGAAUAUACCCUUUAUGUUCAGGAAUGCAGUCUAUCAUUCAGAGUUAAUUUCUUUCUAGGCUCUUUGACAAUCAGUUUUUCCCUGGAUCAGUUCAGUACAUAUGCAUUGAGCACCUGUGUGCCAGUCAGCCGAGCUAUCACAUUGCACAAUUCUAAGAAGCACCAUUCAUGUCUCAUCAUAUUUCUAUGCUCUGGGAGUUGCCUUUCACAUAGAAUAUGUGUGAUUGUUAUCCCUAGAAUUGUGCAGUGAGGCAAUUGGCUAGGUGCUGUGCUGCUUUUUCUUUCUUUCUUUUUUUUUUUAAGAGACAGAGUCUUGCUGUGUUGCCCAGUCUGGAGUGCAGUGGUGGCAUGAUCUUGCCUCACUGUAACCUCUGCCUCCUGGGUUCAAGCUGUUCUCAUGCCCCAUUCUCCCUUGUAGCUGGGAUUACAGGCUUACACCAUCGCACUUGGCAAAUUUGUGUAUUUUUAGUAGAGACAGGAAUUCACCAUGUUGGCCAGGCUGGUCUUGAACUCCUGACUUAAAGUGAUCCACCUGCUUUGGCCUCCCAAAAUGCUAGGAUUAUAGGUGUGAGCCACUGCACCGGGCCAUGUGCUACUUUUUCUUCCUUCCAUCCUUCCUCCCUUCUUCAGUGUAAAUAUGAGAUUAAUUUGUGAUACCUUACUUUAAAGAACUUAGAGUUCAGUAAAGGAAGCAGGUAUAGAAAGUGCUAUGAUAAAGCUAUACAUAGGAUGGUAUAGAACCACAGACUAGGGGCACUUAAAAUGGGCAAGAAAAUAGCCUUUGUAAAUAAAAUAGAGGCAAGAGAUAUAAUGCUUUACCUGCAAAGAGCUAUAAAUACAGCCAUGUACCAUAUAAUGAUGUUUCAGUUAGUGAAGGACCACAUACGAGGGUGGUCAGAACAGCAGGCUAUACCAUAUAGCCUAGGUGUGUAGUAGGCUAUACCAUAUAGCCUAGGUGUGUAGUAGUAGGCUAUACCAUAUAGCCUAGGUGUGUAGUAGUAGGCGAUACCAUAUAGCCUAGGUGUGUAGUAGUAGGCUAUACCAUAUAGCCUAGGUGUAUAGUAGUAGGCUAUACCAUAUAGCCUAGGUGUGUAGUAGGCUAUACCAUAUAGCCUAGGUAUGUAGUAGUAGGCUAUACCAUAUAGCCUAGGUGUGUAGUAGUAGGCUAUACCAUCUGGGGUUCCUGUCAGUACAGUAUGAUGUUCACAUAAUGAUGAAAUCACCUAACAAAGCAUGUCUCGAAAUGUAUCCACAUUGUUACGUAACACAUGACUGUAGUUAAUUGUUACAAUUGAAAUACUAGAUGUACUCAUUGAAAUCCAGAAUUCCCAUUAUCUGGAUUAUUUAAUAUCGUUCAGGAAAUUUUUGCCAGUGCAAUGGUGCAUGAAACAAUGUCUUUUAGAAAUGAGGUGGCCAGAUUUCUAUUUGCAGAUAAUAAUUGUAUAUCUAAAAAUCCUAGAAAAAGAAAUGAUAACAAAUGGAGCUACUUAACCUUUACAUGUUGAAUGCUGCCACUGUUAAAAUUUCUGAGGGGGUAUAAUAGAUAAACUAUCCCAUAGUUCAUCUGGAAAAAUAAGGUGGUGAAAAUUGCUAAGAAAUUUUUGAAAGGGUAAUGUAAACCUAGAUUAACUGUUUUUGAAAGGUAGUACAGAACUGAAUGCACAACUAGAUAUCAAUGGUAUGUACUCACCCAGAAAAAAGACUUCAGUACAUACAUGUGAGGGCUUAAAACAUUGUUAUAAAGACGGGAUCACAAUGGGAAAAGGAUUAUUCAAUAAGUAGGGCAGGCAUUCUCUAUGCCUGCUAGGGAAGUGUGACUUGUUAUACUCUUUAUGUACAGCAAUUGGCAGUCUGUGAAACUUUUAAAUUCAUAUACAUAACCUUUUGCCCUGCAAUUCCACUUCUAGAAAUUUAUCCUACCAAACAAAGCACAUAGAUGUGCAAAAGUAUGUAUUUACAAGUAUAUUCUUUGCAACUUGGUAAUGUCAAAGAAUUGGAAGCAACCUAAAUAUCUGCCAUAGGUAGGAUAACCAUAUGCUUUGGCUUUUUGAACACUACCAGUUUAUACCUGCUGUUCUUGGAUAAUUAUUAAUAGUGCUUUCAUUCUCAAUGUCUCACUUUAGAUAAUAAAUUACAGAGGAUUGGUGAAACUAAUUUGCCCAAUGGAAAAAGGAAUGAAGAAGUGCUUUAGGUACUGAGAUGAAAAGAUCUCUAAGGCAUAAUAAUGUUUAUUGAGAAAAGCAUGGUGUCAAACUGUAUGGCAUGCUACAAUUGAUGUAUAAGAAGAAAAAAUGUGUAUGUAUUCCUAUUUGUUUGUAUAUGGUAGACUGUCUCUGAAGACAUAUAUGGAAGAACCUGAUCACAUUGGUAGUCUCCAAGGAGCAGAACUAGAUACCUGGGGGAUAAGGAUCCCAGGAGUGAGCCUUUUCAUUGUAAACUUCAUUGUACUUUGAGUUUUUAACUGUUCAAAAAUAAUAAAAUUAGAAAUAAAAUAUUUCAACAAACAAUAAAAUGGGAUAUUUGGGGAAGAAAGUUGUCUCAGGGCUCUCCAAAGAAGCAG